ACUCGUUCCCGGGAACCGAACCUGGAAUCCCCGGCGGCAGUGGGGCUGUUGCUGUUGCUGUGGCUGUCGCUGCCCGUCAGGCUGCCUUCUUUUGUCGUUUCCCAGCGCUGCGCAGGACUUCUCCUGGCGGCGCUGCGGAUCCAGGGGGUCGGCUGCCAGGUACAGGGGUUGAGGCUGGGCAAACGCCGCGAAACUAUCGCUCUUCCCCGUCCCGCUUCCGCGCCUGUCCACCCUGGGUAACGGAACCAGCAUCGCGGUAGGGACAUCCUCGCUAGGCCCGGCCGGACCAUUCCUCAGGGUGGGCCCUUUCCGAAGCCGGGACCGCUCCUGCUUGUCGGCAUCGCUCCCCACAGGCCGACGUCGAGAGGGCCUGCUUUACUCCUCCUCUUUCUCCUCCUUCUCCCGCGGCUUCUGCGCGGAGAGGCGUCGCCCGGGAUCUGGGUUUUGGAAGAAGGAUCUUUGUGGGAAGACAGGGUGAAUUUAUCACAGAGGAAUAACGAGGGAGAGGAGAAAGGUUUGUCCAUGGGGCUGCUAGACUAGUGGAAGGGGAUGCGGUGCGUCAAGGGAAAAUUAGGUUGAAAACAAAUGUCGUGUAUUAAUCUAAAAACAUUUGGAAUGGUUCUAAAACUGGAUGAUGAGUUAAACCAAAUAUUUACUAAAUAUUUACUAAAUUGCCCUCAUUCAGCAGGCUCUUAUAGAAUACUAUAGUGUUAAGAUUAAAGUUUUUAAGAGUAUAUUGAAGUCGUUAAGUGUAUAUUUACUCCUUAAAAGCUACAUAUUCCAAGAAAGACCUUUGGCUUCCAGAAAAAAAAAAUGUUUUAGUGGGUAAAACUCUGACUCCUUCCUUCUCAAAUAGGUGACUUGUGCCCUGGAGUUAGGGAGCCUUGUGCUACAGAUUAUGUGAAGCCAUGAAAUAAACGUGGUAAAUUUUAUUGAGGGAAGCAACAGAGCAGCUUUUGUAUUAAAAGGAGCCUGAGUACGCUAUGGGGUAGAAGCCAAAAUUUGUAUGAAGUGUUGGUUUAAAAAAAAUUUUUUUUGUAACUUUCUUGAAGUUUAUCUCCGGAAACUCUGCCCUCAACUUGGAGACUAGGAGGAUUCUGUACAGUAUAUUUCCUUGAGAUACUUUAUUGGAAAAGUUUAAGAGGCACAGAGUCCAGAAUGAUUGGCAUCAGAGCCCAAAGUAGUUUGUGGUAUUUUUUUUAAUCUGUAAUAUUGCUAUGAACUUGAAAAUGUUUUCUGUGCAAAAUACAUCAAAACUAAAAUGUACUUGAUACCCAACUUAAUUAACAUGGUACCUAUUGUAGAAAGACCAAACUGAAAAUUUAGCCUUUGGCACAAUCUAGAAGUAAGCAGAGAAGGGGGUUAAGAUGCCUUUCAUUAUGUUAACGUUUAAUCCUGAGAGUUUACAUAAAAAGCCAGAUUUCUGGGUCUUUGAGAAAAAUGAGAUCUGGCAACUACUAGUUCCAUACCACGUGGCAACCAGUUGGCAGCUCCCCUCAGACUAGCAUGCUGUCAUUUUUGCCACAGUUCCUUCCUCAUCAGUUUUUAUAGCAUCACAUUGAUCAGUGGAUUCAGAUACCUGUAUCAUGGGUAAACAAACCUCUAUCAUGGGCCCAAUUUUCUAUUGUUGUUUCUUUACAUUUGUCAUGCACUCUCAUAGAUAUGUCAGCUUUGACUUCAUUUAAAAAGGAAUAAUCUGCAAAUGUGUUUGACUUCUUGAGAUGAAAGGCAGCAUUUUCAAAUAAAUUAUAAAGAGACUUUGGAAGAUAUUGAGAUGUGUAAAUUCAAGAAAAAUGUAGGAUUCCUUGGAAAUAACACAUUAGUACUGAUAAAAGAUACUGUAUAUGCUGUAGUUCUGAUGAUUGUGAAACAAGUGCUAUUAUAUAAUGUGUGUUACUAGCAUUUCCUGAUUUUGCAUUCUAAAUUAAAUUUAAAAGUAGAGAAAUGGACAUUGUAUAAAAUAUCCACAACCAAUUUAAUAUGCGGCCAUGCUUGGCCGGGCACCGUGGCUCACGCCUGUAAUCCCAGCACUUUGGGAGGCCCAGGCGGGUGGAUCACGAGGUCAGGAGUUCAAGACCAGCCUGGCCAACAUGGUGAAACCCCGUCUCUACUAAACAUACAAAAAAUUAGCCGGGUGCGGUGGCAGGCGCCUGUAAUCCCAGCUACUCAGGAGGCUGAGGCAGGAGAAUCGCUUGAACUCGGAGGGCGGAGGUUACAGUGAGUGGAGAUCGCGCCACUACACUCCAGCCUGGGUGACAGAGUGAGAGUCUGUCUCAAAAAAAAAAAAAAAAGUGUCCAUGCUUUUAAUAUUAUAGUAUUGUAAUAUUUAACUUCUCAAGAACUUAAUUUAUAGAGAUUUAAUACAACAUUAGUUGUAUGGUGUGUUUUAAGAGCACUAGAUAGAUAGGUCAGGCCCAUCCAAAGAAUUAACUAUAUCUUUUUGUUGUUAAUCUGGAUUUACAACACUUGAUUAUCCAGGAAUGGAUUAACUGAUGACCAGGUUCUGACCUCACUCACUGCCCAAUUGCCUUCUAAACCACUGAUAAUGGAGCUUAAGCUUUGAGGCAGGAGAUGAUGGCAGUUGGAGAAAGAAGAAAUUAAGUUGCUGUAUAUGUCUUGUUUCCUAAAGACAAAAAAAAAUGGAGGAAUCUGUAAACCAAAUGCAGCCACUGAAUGAGAAGCAGAUAGCCAAUUCUCAGGAUGGAUAUGUAUGGCAAGUCACUGACAUGAAUCGACUACACCGGUUCUUAUGUUUCGGUUCUGAAGGUGGGACUUAUUAUAUCAAAGAACAGAAGUUGGGCCUUGAAAAUGCUGAAGCUUUAAUUAGAUUGAUUGAAGAUGGCAGAGGAUGUGAAGUGAUACAAGAAAUAAAGUCAUUUAGUCAAGAAGGCAGAACCACAAAGCAAGAGCCUAUGCUCUUUGCACUUGCCAUUUGUUCCCAGUGCUCCGACAUAAGCACAAAACAAGCAGCAUUUAAAGCUGUUUCUGAAGUUUGUCGCAUUCCUACCCAUCUCUUUACUUUUAUCCAGUUUAAGAAAGAUCUGAAGGAAAGCAUGAAAUGUGGCAUGUGGGGUCGUGCCCUCCGGAAGGCUAUAGCGGACUGGUACAAUGAGAAAGGUGGCAUGGCCCUUGCUCUGGCAGUUACAAAAUAUAAACAGAGAAAUGGCUGGUCUCACAAAGAUCUAUUAAGAUUGUCACAUCUUAAACCUUCCAGUGAAGGACUUGCAAUUGUGACCAAAUAUAUUACAAAGGGCUGGAAAGAAGUUCAUGAAUUGUAUAAAGAAAAAGCACUCUCUGUGGAGACUGAAAAAUUAUUAAAGUAUCUGGAGGCUGUAGAGAAAGUGAAGCGCACAAGAGAUGAGCUAGAAGUCAUUCAUCUAAUAGAAGAACAUAGAUUAGUUAGAGAACAUCUUUUAACAAAUCACUUAAAGUCUAAAGAGGUAUGGAAGGCUUUGUUACAAGAAAUGCCGCUUACUGCAUUACUAAGGAAUCUAGGAAAGAUGACUGCUAAUUCAGUACUUGAACCAGGAAAUUCAGAAGUAUCUUUAGUAUGUGAAAAACUGUGUAAUGAAAAACUAUUAAAAAAGGCUCGUAUACAUCCAUUUCAUAUUUUGAUCGCAUUAGAAACUUACAAGACAGGUCAUGGUCUCAGAGGGAAACUGAAGUGGCGCCCUGAUGAAGAAAUUUUGAAAGCAUUGGAUGCUGCUUUUUAUAAAACAUUUAAGACAGUUGAACCAACUGGAAAACGUUUCUUACUAGCUGUUGAUGUCAGUGCUUCUAUGAACCAAAGAGUUUUGGGUAGUAUACUCAACGCUAGUACAGUUGCUGCAGCAAUGUGCAUGGUUGUCACACGAACAGAAAAAGAUUCUUAUGUAGUUGCUUUUUCCGAUGAAAUGGUACCAUGUCCAGUGACUACAGAUAUGACCUUACAACAGGUUUUAAUGGCUAUGAGUCAGAUCCCAGCAGGUGGAACUGAUUGCUCUCUUCCAAUGAUCUGGGCUCAGAAGACAAACACACCUGCUGAUGUCUUCAUUGUAUUCACUGAUAAUGAGACCUUUGCUGGAGGUGUCCAUCCUGCUAUUGCUCUGAGGGAGUAUCGAAAGAAAAUGGAUAUUCCAGCUAAAUUGAUUGUUUGUGGAAUGACAUCAAAUGGUUUCACCAUUGCAGACCCAGAUGAUAGAGGCAUGUUGGAUAUGUGCGGCUUUGAUACUGGAGCUCUGGAUGUAAUUCGAAAUUUCACAUUAGAUAUGAUUUAACCAUAAGCAGCAGCACGAUCCAGAGAUCCAUUGCCAUCAGUGAUCUCACUAAAAAUAUACAGCUACUUCCCAGCUAAUCUCCACCCAAUGAAUGAUGAUGGUAUAGUAUGUGCAUAAUGGAAAGUUACCUUACUGAAAAAAAAAAAAGAAGGAAAAAUAAGAUGGGCCCAAAGGUCUAUCUACUAAACUAGCUCUUGGGGAAAUAGCUUCAGGAUACUGUAGUUUCCUCUAUCUAAUAGAGAACUUUUUGUUAACAGACACUGUAAAAUAGUUUUGCUUUGUUGAAUAAUACGUGUGUACCUAAAAGAGGUAAGAGCAAAAAGUGUAAUUCCACAUCAUGUUACUUGAGAAGUGCUUAACGUUUUCUUAAAUGUUUUCAUUGGGAAAGGACAGCUUUGAUAAUGUCCAAAUACUCUGAAAUGCACUAGACCAUAUAACUGUGAUGAAAUAUGAAACUCAUCUGUAAACUUUUAUACCAAGGGGGUAAAAAAAAAAACUAAGGCAUUUGAUUAAAUUAUGAAUGAGUUUUACAAAUUCCUUUCAGAGUUUUACUAAGAUCACACAAAUAACAGCUUUCUUAUUCAGUGAAAAAGAUAUUUUAUUUCUGAUGUUUUAUUUGCACUUGUGGAAUAUGUUACCAUUAAUCAGAAACAUCAUGGCAACCCCUAAGAAUAGACUAAGUUUGUGUUGGCUGAGGGAUUCUAUUUGGUUUGCUUUUUUUUUUUUGCUUUGUUAUAUUUUAUUGCUACAAGGGGUGUGACUUGAUAAUGAUUUCCUCUGAAUUAUAAUAACAUAGCCAGAUGUAGUCUCACACUGUUUUUCAUACUCUUAAGUGUAAAUAAUAUAAAAUGUUUCAAGCGCUUAACUCCCCCUCAUUCACAAAGUAUAACAAUUAAAAUCUCAACUAUAACCAGUUUAGCUUUUUCCUUACUUUUAAAAUAAAAUUUUUUACUUUUAACUAUUUUUUUAGUUAAUAUUUUUAAAAGUAUACAUGUCAAUGGCCUCUUUGUCCAUUAUUCAUUUUGUGGCAAAAUAUUCUUCUUUGAUAGUGUAAACAAAUAAUAAAGCAAUCUAGGUCCUUUAGGUUUGAAAGGCAAUUUUUGAGUAGCAUAUUACCAGCUAGCCAGUCACUAGGAAUUUUUUUCAGUAUUAUUUGUAUGUAUUAAACUUUUCAUUACACUAAAGUGCAUUAUUUUAUUGAGCAAGUAUCCUUCAUUGUGAGGUUUAACAUUAAAGCAAUCUGUUGAAAUGCCAUUAUCUUUGCUCAUAAUUUUAUUAUGGCCGUCUAAGGUAGCUUACACAUAAAACCUGUUUGCGUAUCUGUUGUUCUCUAAAUAUUAAUUGAAGAUUUACUGAGGAUUUGUAAGGUCCUUCUCGCUGUUAUGUGAAAAGUCAAACUGUAGUUAAUGUAAAUUAUAGCCUUUUAGGUGCUUGGGGGUUAGAGGGUUUAUGUUUUUUGGGAAAGGGGGACUUUAGUAGUCUGAGGAUUUCUGUACAUAUUUUCUUCUGUUUUAUGUGAAAUUUGGGCUCUGGGAAUAAGAAAAUAUUCCUUUCAAAUUUAUUUGACAUAUUAAUGCUGGUUUUGAUAUGUACCCAUUCCUUCAAGGCAACUGGUAUCAGUUUUUAAGUGUGAUUUACCUGAGAUAUUUUUGUUCAGCAAAGCUCAUAGCACCCUCACCCCCACUCCAGACAUGCAUUGCUUCUGAUGUUGUUCACGUUUUUAACCCUGUCAAGCAUUGAACUGAAUAUAUUAGCUACUUUUGACACAUUAAAAUAUUACGUUCAGAUUGAAUUUAAAGUUUAAAGAAACUAAUAGAAUUACGUAAUAGUUAUUGAAUUGUUUAAGUAAACCCAAGAUCUUAAAAAUUAUAACAUGAUCAUUUUAUUCCUAAUAGAAAUGUUAAAUAGAAUAUAGUACAAAAGUGCAUUACCUUCAGUUGUGUACUAUUUCCAUAAUACUUUUAGACAAAUAUAUCUAUAAGUUAAUAUUAAAUCCAUCAAGGAUACAAGAUUGGAUGGAUAUGACCUUUCUGAAGUAUUUAGGUAGGUCUAAUUAAAUGGACUAGGGUAACAUUUAAGAAAGAAAGGAUAAGUAGGAGAAGCUACCACAGAAGGUAACUUUUCAAAUCAUGGCAUAUUUGAGCUGGAAGAAACCUUAGAAACCUAAAAGCUAAUUUUUUAAAUUUUUGUUAGAGAGCUGAGGUCCAAGACAGAGUGUGAUUUUGAAGUACUAUAACCUAGAAAUCUUGGUCUCUUCAUUCCUGUGCCAGAAUUUAUUUCCCCACAACAUGGGAAUACAUGGUCUCAGAAGAGUAGAGGAUAAAAUAAAAUUAUUUAAGACUUUUACCUUAUUGAGUUAUUAGGAAAUAAUGUAUAUACGAUUGCUUUAGGAGUAGAAAAAUAGAAUGGGAACAUGUAUAAUCUUGUAAUUCAUAGGAAUCCUCAAGCACAAUUAACCUGUGUUGCUAUAUAUAUCUACAUAUAUAGAGAAAAAACAAAAACUUUACCUCAUUAUGAAUAAAAUGUACUGAAGUGAUAAGUUUUUUAUUUCCUGAGUUACUUUUAGGAUUACUGUUAAAUUAAUAUUUGGGAAAAUACUGCUUUUAAAAACAAUCCUGCAAGAAUAAACAAACUUUAUUUCCUAGGUAGUAUGUAAAUAGUUCCAGGAUAUAGUUGUAAUUAGUAAAACAAAAACUAAUCUUAUAAUCCCACCCUUUAUUAGUUGAAAGUUCUUGGAAAUUCCAUUUAUUAAUACUUAUAUUAUUUAGUAAUCUAUCUUAUGAGAGUGUUAGUGAGGCAAGAUGCUAGUGAAUGGAAUUUAGUGUUACCCUUUGACACCUCCUUUGCUUUAUCUAACUUACUGUGUGACUGUAGACAACCAGUUUAACCUAAGUGAUUUGAUUAUUUUUAUCCUUAAAAAGUAACAUAUCUGUGCUUGGAUCAUAGAAGAAUCAGUGAUUUAAUAUUUGUAUAAAAAUUGAAACUGGGAAGAGGGCUUGCAAUACAAGUUAGAAUUCUUUUUUUUUUUGGUUAAAAACAUUCUUGUUAAUAAGAUACGUAUUUCAAAAGAUAAAAUGUUUUAGAAAAAUAGCUCACUCAAUAGGCCUAACAGUGUUUUAAAACAUUCCUGUUCAGAGUAGAAAAAUUUAGAAGAAAAAUUUUCACAGCUAAAGUAUUACCCAAAAAGUCACUAUUCUCUACUGAAGAGGGAGAAAAAAUAUACUCCAAGAUCUUCUUGGACAGACCUAGAAAAACAAGCUUAUACUCUGAGGAAAUGCUGUUAACAAACUUUUUUUUUUGAGACAGGCUAUCCCUCUGUCACCCAGGCUGGAGUGGCAUGAUCACAGCUCACUGCAGCCUUGACCUCCCAAGUUCAAGUGAUCUUCCCAAGUAGCCAGGAACACUGGUGUGCACUGCACUACCACGCCUGCUUUUUUUUUUUUUUUUUUUUUUUUUUUUUUUAAGAGACAACGUCUCACUGUGUUGCCCAGGCUGGUGUCAAACUCCUGGGCUCAAGGGAUCUUCCUGCCUUGGCCUCCCGAAGUGCUGGAAUUAGAGGCAUGAGCCACUGCACCCAGCCAGCAAACAUUCUCUUAAUCUUUUAAAGUAACCAGUAAAUCUACAAAUAGUAAAGUACUAUUUUCAUCAGGGAUUUUUUUUUUCUUAUUUUCUAGAUUUUACAGAAACAAUGUGAAAUUAUUUUGGAAAGAUAAGGUAGGAUUCUUGAAUAAAUCUGAAGGUCUCACAAUUAAGUGAGAAACACCUUUAAAAGCAUAGUAAAGCUACACCUAAAUAACUAAAGCCUAAAUCAUUGUAAUGUUUUGUUGGACUUACUUUAACUUGACCUGUUGUAGCCACAAAUAACAAAUUUCUUGGUAACUGAUGCUAUUACAGUAGGUAAUCAAAAAUGAAAAAUUCUAGUCUUAUAUACUGCAGGUUUGGGGUGAUUGUUAAGGCACUAUCCCCUCUGGAGAAAUGUCAUAUGGCAUCAGUGUAAACAUGCACAAGAAAGAAUUUGUAAAAAAAAAUGACAGGUUAAUCAAUGAAAUUAGUUGUAUUUACUGUUUGGAUUUUAUUUAGUGUUUCCUUGAUGUCUGUUUCCUCAUCUCUUAUUUGUUGGAAGAUUACUUUUCUACCUCUUUUUUUUCUUUUAAAAUUCCUUUCUUACAUUUCUGUUGUUUCUUUUUCUAGUCCUUCUCUAUCUGGAUAAUAAAAUGAAUGACAGGAAAGUCACCCACAUAGAGGUUUGGGAUGAACCUUUUGCAGAUUGCUUUUUGUUUCAUACAAGUAUAAGAUCAUAUUUUCUUUUUCAACUUAGUAAUAGGCAGGCUUCUUGGAACAAUAAGUAGAUUGAUACACUCCUCCCCAAAUCAAAUUAUAUUGUAUAUCUUUUAUAUUAGAUGUUUGCAGAAAUUCUGUGGCCUUUAAGAUCAGUUAUUCAGCCUUUGUAAUUAUGUUAUCUAGCUAUGUUGAAAAGAUAAGUGCUUACUAUAUAAGCACUCUUAGAAAAAUAAUUAACUGAUUACUCUUUCAGAAAAUAGCAGGUGUCUCAAUGCUUUUUUUCCAUAAUUAUAAAGACCAUUGUCAAAAUCUUUGGUUUACUAAAUAUUUCACUGAGCAUAUAUAGAGAUACGUUGCUUGUGGCAUAAAAAGUCUUGUAGAUAACUUACUCACAUUUGGCUUUUUUUUAAUUGGUGCAUUUUUUAAUUUGCUUUUUUGAAAAUUAUGAAGUUAAAAUUUAAUUCUAAGGUAGUAUUUUUCAUGUAUAAAACUAAUAAUGUAGUUAAGCAUACUGUUUGAAUAAAAUUAUAAUAAAUGGCACAAUUCCUUAAACCCUGAAAAUACCAAGUUAUAUUGGAAAAUAGUGGAAAGAAAAAACUAGUGGAGAACAUCUUAGAAAAUUCUAUUGUGGAAAUUACGAUGAUUAUUUUCAGUGAGAAUGAAUUUAUAUAUACAACAAAAAUAUACAAAAGCUAACCUUCUCAUCCUAAAAAGAUUUUUCCCUUUGCUUCUGUUUUAUUUAGCCCUGCCAUGCACCACAUUAAUUUUAUGAACAUAAAUGAUAUUUAACUUUUCUUUUUUUUUUUUUUUUUGAGACAGAGUCUCACUCCGUCACCAGGCUGGAGUGCGGUGGCGCGAUCUCAGCUCACUGCAACCUCCAUUUCCCAGGUUCAAGCAAUUCUCCUGCCUCAGCCUCCCAAGUAGCUGGGAUUACAGGCACGCGCCACCACGCCCACCUAAUUUUUGUAUUUUUAGUAGAGACGGGGUUUCACCAUGUUGGUCAGGCUGGCCUCGAUCUCGUGACCUCGUGAUCUGUCCGCCUCGGCCUUCCAAAGUGCUAGGAUUACAGGCGUGAGCCACCGCACCUGGCCAACUUUUCAUCUUAAGUUGUUUAAAUUUAUGCACUUUUAGAUAUCAGAAUAUAUGCUUGAACAAAGGAAAUAGUAAAUUAGCUAUAUGUCUGCUGGUUUCACUUCGAUGUGGAUAUGGAUAUGUGGAUAAAGACAGUAAAUGAAAUUAAAACCCUGCUGUUUUAAAUAUCAUUACCAGAUAUAAUUGAGGGAAUAUUAUAUCAACAAACAUAUUGAAACUUGGCUUUAUUUGUAACGUAAACUAUAUAUAAUCCAUACGUAGCCAAAUUAGAUUUAAAAUAUACAAUUAAUGAAUAGUACUCAAAGUGUUUUUGUUGCACUGUUACUCUGAAUAUGGACUCUCUAUAUCUGGUAUGGCGUGACUGGGCAUAACUUCUGUAAUGUAUUUCAGUUAUAUGUUUUUCCUUUUAUUGCCAGCUUCUGAUAAUGAAAUUUUCCAAAGGGAUGAGAUAUAAGAAUCAUCUUUUAUAAAAACCAGUGGGGAGUGGGGUAUUAUAAUCUAGUUCUAAACUGUCCAUUUGCUUUAUAUAAAGGCUUUGAUUUCAAUAACUGACCAUUUGAUGAAUAUUUAAAUUACACAGAAUAAUGUCUACAUAGAAUAAACUUAAGUAUUCAAGAGCCUUAAAGUGAAAAAAUGAACCUUUUGACUGCCUUAAAAUACUACUUGCUCUGUAAUUCAGGCAUACUAGUUACUUUCCUUGGGGUCUGUUUAAAUAAUGCCUUAAUAGUGUUCUAAUGUUUCUGAAAUACAGAACUCAAAGGGUCUUUUAGAGCUUUUAAUUUUACAUAGUGAAUGGAAAUUUAAGUAUUACAUUUUAAAACCUGAUUGUACAUUGGUAAUUUAAACAUCCAAUAACAGGAAAAUCUAGAUACAGUGAUGUGUUAUACAUACAUGACUGUUAACAUCAGUAAUAUUUUAUGAUAGUUUAAGGUUUUUUAUUGUUUUCUAUAACAAGUUAUCCAACAGGUUGGACUUUGUAACAUGAUAUCCAAGGACCAAGUUGCAUAUUUAACAUCGAAUGAAAAUGUAGUUGUACAGUUCCAAAAAUAAUUAAUUUUUUAAGGGAAUUUUUCAAGACAAAAGGCAAAUAUUUUGUUUCAAACCUACAAGCAAAU